GUCUUUUCUUUUCACAUGGUAGCUGCCGAGCAGUUUGUUCGGCUUUUUAUUUAUUCCUACGUGAGCAGACCCACUACACUUCUUGCAUAUAAACAGUGAAAAUUACAAUAUGAAGGACUUAUUAUUCCUUCUUUUGGAGUAAUUUUGCUGCUGGUCAAAGCCUGGCUCAUUGUGCAAGGAAGGGGGACCAUCCUCUGCAGGUAAUUCCACUGCUUCAAGGUGCUCCUCGCCUGCUUGCAGAUAUCAGACCCCAGCUCAUCUCAGACCUCAGCCCCUGAGGCCAAGCAAACAUACAUCAUCAUGGAGGCUGCAGACGUAGCUCACCGUGCCCACAUGUGAACUUCGGCCAACACACCACAACAGGGACUCUGCCCACUGAAUCCCCUGUGAUUCCUCAAUCCUGUCCUGGUCAUACCCCACUGGGUUUUGUGAGGCUAUUUAGGAAGAUAAGUUUCCCUCACUGAAGAAAAGAGAGACAGCAUGAAAGAAAACAAUGGCCCCAAAGGAGGAAUUUGUGAUUGACAUAAAUGGGAAUGUUCCCUUGGGAGCAUCAUGUAUCAUCAAACAAGCAAACCUCCAGGUCAUUUAUUUCUCCACCUGUUUACCUGCUAUGGAAAGAAGAUGCAUUUAAGUUUCCUGCAGUUUCACCCUGGAAAUUAAUGCUCUGGGAAACAAAAAGCUGUAUGUUCUAGACGUAGCAGGUUUCUUUUGGAAUUCACUCAUUGGGAGUCUGGCACUACCCCCUAAAUGGUACUUUUGUUGUCUUUUUGUUCAAGACAGCCAGCUUCUUCCAAGAUCAGAACCGCGUGCCAGCCUCCCUUGAUAAACCGCCUACCAGCUCUCUUGGUAGAUCAGAUGUUUAAUAGUUAGCCUAACUCAUUUGUUUUUCCAAGGAGCAAUUAUGACUACAAUGAAUUAAUAUUUUAACUGCAGGGAAAGCAUUACAGAUAGUUCCUACGUAGACUCUAGAGGCUGGGAAUGGCCAACAGGAUUUCCCAUACUAAGAGGAGAGGACCACUCCAUCCUGGCCAGCAGUUCUCUAUGAUUGAAAUACUAUCAUUAGAUACUGCUCCAAAGACCUAAGGGGAGAUGUGCCUAGGAGAAGUGUAUGGUCCUGAUCCUUCCCACUGAGGCUCAAUGGCCCAGCAAAAUAUGAAAGUGAGACCUGUGCUUCUAAAGCGUAACAGUCUAGAAUCAGUGGAGUUUGUGAAACAACCUCACCACCGCAGGAGCAAAUCCCAGCAGGUGAGAUUCAAGGAAGAUGGGACCACUAAGAAUCCAACUGGCCUAGCUGAGGUUGACGUCCAAACUCCAGAAGACCCGGCUGUGAUGGGGAAGACUCAAGCAACCAGGCACCAUCUUCCCCCCACCUACUCGCUCUCCUUCCCCAGGUCCCAGAAGGCAGGGGGCUUUCGCAACAUUGCAAUCCAAACUUCCCCCAGUCUCAGGAAGCAUUUCCCAGUUUUCAAAAGGAAGAGACUCACAGCCAGUAAGUCCCUGGUGGAAAUGCCAACAGCCUCCCAAAGUGCCAUCCAGGUCAACGGUAACCUCUCUGAACAGGACAUUGUGUCUUCUGACCUUGCCUACUUAAGGUUGGCUCAGCAUCUUGAGGAUGGGCCUCGAAGGGUCAAGGUGUCCCAUGCAUUCCUCCCAAGGGUCCCCAAGGUGCAAAGCAAUGGUCCUGUUAGCAUAUGCUUGGAAGCAGGAACUUGGAGGUCCUUAGAGAAAGCCACAGCUGCCAUUCAGGUUCCAGAUGAUAUUUAUCACAGUCCUUCCUGGGAAGCUAGAGAGUCUGCUCUCAGCCCAGACAGGUCAGCUGAAGUAAGUAACUCCAUACACCCUUUGGAUGACACACGUCCAGGUGAUGGGAGAAGGGUGACUCCACUAGAUUCAGAAAAAUCCACCUCCUGCUUAAAUGCCACCAGCGUUGCCAGCCACACACCAGGCACAGAGGAACUUAAACCUGAAUUGCUUUUGCCCAAAGACAACUCAGAUGACAAAGACCUUGGCUCACUGUCAUCUCAGUCAAAGGAAACGUGUGUUCCUUCAUCUCCACGGACUCACAGUUCCCCCUCACAAGGCUCCCACAGCCAGCCAGCCCACCCAGGAAGAGCCUCAGACUGUCCUUCAUCAAGUAACAAUCACCAGAAUCUGGUGUCACUCAAAACUAACAGUGCAUCGAAAUCUGCCCCUGGGUGUCAGGAGCAGACGGCAAACAACCCCACCGAGUCAGACACACUGGAGUUUCCAAAUUGUCCAGGAAGUAAUCAUCUCCCAUCCUCUCUUUCAAGGAGUGAGACCAAACUUCAGAGCAACAGGGAGAUUAGUGACAUUAAUCAAAUUCACCUGGCACGGGGUGAACUCUGCGACCUCCAAGGCCGACUGCAAUCUGUGGAGGAAUCUCUGCACUCGAACCAAGAGAAAAUUAAAGUCCUUUUGAAUGUAAUUCAAGACUUGGAGAAAGCUCGAGCUCUCACUGAAGGGCGCAACUUUUAUCGAACUGGCCAAGAUCUCAACAAUUGCAGUACCUGCCAGAACACGGCGUGCAUCAUAUACAGGUACCUGGCCACAAGCGAGGCCUGCUCUGUAGACCAUAAAGCCAUAGGGUCCGCUGAACACUCUAGCAAACUUUUAAAUGCAAAAAGUCAAGAGAGGCAAAAACAAGUGUAGAGUAUGAUUUUCGGCAGCAGGAAGGCAGGUUCCAUGAAGUUUUGCAGAGUCUGGAGGAAGCAGAGCCAGUUGAGGAGGCAUCGCCCCCACCAAAGUCCCCAGCAGAACCCCCAGCCCCGGAAAAGCAGGACUUAAGGCGGAAAACCAAGAAGGUGAAAAAGAAAUGCUUCUGGUGGAUCUGAGCUGGUUGGGACCAUCCCCCAGCCCCCCAACUCCACGCACUUCCCUGAGAUGGGAAAUCCACUGCACUUAAGGCCUGCCCUGCUUCUUUGCAAAGGCCCUGGGCUGUGAGCCCCUUGGCCUGUGAAACAGAAGAGCCUUGGAGCUGAUGUAGCCGCUGCUGGACACCUGACCACGAUCCUUACCUGAGUGCGUGCGACUGCUUGCUGAGGGCUUCACGGACACUAGAGUGACCGCUUGCCAAGUUCCCUGUCACACUCAGCCAGAACUCAUGCUGAGUUUUAAGACCAGAUUCCCACCACGAGCAAAACCCCACACUACACCUUCCAACACCUCCAAGAUGCCAAGCACUUCCUUCCCAUCCUGGGUUCAUAAACCCAAAAGAAAAAAAUAGUGUUGUGCAGACCCGGAAGGUAGAGGGAGGUUAUAGGUUAUAAGCAGGUACCAUAGAAAAAAAUGAGAUAAACUGGCAGUUUUCUAAGAUAUCAGCAUACAUAAUAAGCACAAGAGAAGUGGGCAGGGCAUAAAAUGCUUAUGCAAGAUCACCCUGGUGUGUUGGGUUGUUUUCCUUUUUAAUUAGCCCCUUGAUCCCAAAUUAAGGCUCUGUCAUCUCAUGGUGCAUGCACCUUUCUGCCUGUGGCAGAGUCAGGCCACCCCAGGGUAUAAACUUGUUGGUGUGGCUGUGCUGGAUAAGUGUAAUUCAAAGAGGAUUUCAGCAGCUGUAGCUGUUCCAGGGCCCACCCUAAACCAUCAUGCUUCUUCUCUGCCUAGGGCCUGAGACCACCUGGCAAAUGGGUGGAAUCUGUUUUUGGUGUGAACUUUAAGACUCCAUAGUUAACUUACCUGCAAUAUUUAAAAUCAUGAGAUCCAGCAACCUGUCCAUCAGUUACAUCUUAUGAGUAACAUAGAUAAGGCUAAGAUAAAACACAACACUGUUUCUCAUCCCUUCAUCCCAGAAACAGCCGUGUAGAUAGGUUCAAACAUAUAUUAAUCGACACAGUCUCCCUUCCUGGUGACCAGACAAUGGUCACCUGAUUGAAAAACUAGCAGGACUAUGGAUGAGGAUAUAGUUUUUUCUAUUUGAGGUUUAAAUAUCUUUCCAUCCCAAAGUCUGAGUUAUUCAAGGUCUGGCUCAUUCUGUUGACAAGACCUACAUACAUGUGGAUCCAGUCAAACUUGCAUGGCUGAACAAACUACUAAAGUAAUAUAAUUAAGUAAUUGCUAUAUACUCUUGUGGAUGAGGGGUAGGAUGGAAAGGCUCAGAUUCCUUCUGGUUGAAUUAAAAUCUCUAUCAGCAUGUGGUUAGAUUGACAUUGCUAGAAAGGGAGCCUGAAACUAAACAUACAUUAAACGAAGAAGGUAUUUUGUAAUUCCCUUGGCUGAAGAUCCAGUGUCUAAGCUAGAAUCUUUGCAGAGCACAGAAUCCUGUGUGUUCGUGGGAUGUACCUACCCCACUGCAAAUUGAGCCUAAUUGAGCAAACCACUCCGAUGGUUUCACCUUCCCCUGUCAUAGUGAUGCAGUGAACAAAGCUAUUUCAGUGAGAAUGAAAGGGAAAUUUGGCAAGGAAUAUCAGCUUGCACUAUUUAAGUCUUGGAAUGUCAUUCAAGAUGUUCUUGUUCUGUUUCUAGUGUAAUGUUUAAGCCCACAGAAUCAGACCGGAAUAUAUAACGUCAUGUUAGAAUUAAGAUAAAUACACUUGUCAUACUUAAGAAGCCACAUUUCAAUAAGAUAUGCUACCACUGGCUAAAAGCCACAGAUUUUUUUUUUCCUGUAUCCAUACGAUCAACUGUCAGUUGGCCCCAGCAAUGGAAAAGAACAGAAUAGAGGAUAAUCCAAUAAAGUGAAAUCAUUUGGGACCUCUUAUGUAAUUUUAUCUUGUAGUAGAGCUUCCAUCUUAAUUUGCUUUGCUUACGCUAAUUUCAUGUGAAUUUAUAUUCUCGGGCAUCAUGCUAGAAUGUAAAUAACCCUGUUCCCAGAAUUAAGAGAUCCAGGCAACCAAGCAGUCUAUACCACUAGCCUUUGGCAAAUGGCUUAAAUUUCCCGGCCUGUUUGUCCAUUCUUGAAUACAGAUAAGAACAUAUGCUUUCCUACUUUAUAAACUCUUAGCACGUUCCACAUUAUGUGAGCUGAGUGACUCAGAGCUGAGCUGGAUUACUGGCCAAAGUUAGCCUGGGAAGAUAAAGAGAUGUUUGAGGUACCUCACACAAAAUUAAUAAGCUGAUGUGGUCAUAGAUAUGUUUCCAGUUGAGGCCCUCACAUGAACCCUUAACUGAAUUAAAUAAAACUGGGACUAGAAAAUGUUGACAUUUUCUGCACUUCCCCAACAAAAAAAAAAGAAAAGAAAAGAAAAGAAAAAAAUAAAUAAAAUGUUGACAUUUCUAGAAAUACAGCCAAACAAGGCUGUACUGAUUCUACACCAAAGCACAACACCGCAUUGCUUGGGCCACUGACCUGAAACUGGGAAGGAGUUCUCUUCUGAAAAAUUGAUAUUUAAAAUCAUUAUGAGGAAAUAGGAUUCCAUAAACAUUUUCCUGAUGAACAAAAAUGGUCGUCUCUAUGUUUAAAACACCACACACACAUAUACCAAAACUGCAUACUCACUUAUUCAUGUGAAAAUCACUGCUUCUUUGUAAAAUAUUACGUAACAUCUACCAUGAUAUUCUACAGAAAUGCUGUACUUGAGGUUAUCUGGUUUGCUGGAGAGAUAUUAACUUAGCAAAAAUUACUUUUAUAAAAUUGAAAGGAAAAAGACCAAUACAUCAACUUAAAUUGCAGGAGUUUAUGUAGCUGCUUUCUCUGUAGUUUAAAAAGCAAUGCAUAAAUGCAUACUCACUAUCCUUGGAACUUAAUACCAGCUCAUCUAUAGAGCACCUUCUUAAAGACGAUGUACUGAUGUAAGGUUUUGUAAAUUUCUAAACUGUUUUAAACGGGAUAUUAUCUUUUGCAAUAAACUUACAUAUUUUUUCUAGGU